AUGCCGCGGCGUCCAGGGUACCCCAGCCCUAGUCUCUCCUCCCAGGGAGCCCGGCGCUUCCCUUACCCGACUGUAGCGAGAACCUCCGGGGAAUCCCUUCUUCCUCCCCCAGUUCCCACACCCAGGACCCAGCUGCGGGGAGGCAUCCCACACAGGAGACGCAGAGGCAGUGAGAUCGGGGCACCACGCUGCCCCCCGCGCGGGGGCCGGCGCGGACCACCGCCUCGAUGUGGUGGCUCACCGCUGGGCUGUAGGGACGCCAGCGGCCGUGCUCGUUCAGCCAUUCCCAGACCACCACGGCCGAGGCCAGGAGCAUGGCGAGCCCGGGGCUGCGGCGCUGCGCGGCCCGCCUCCCGGGCCCCGAGCGCCCGACCUCCUCCGCUUCCUCCUGCGCCGCCGCCUCCGGGCCUCGACCGCGCCCCCUGCCCCGCGCCCCGCCGCCCCGGGCAGCCUCAGCUCCGGCCCAUGGGCUCCUCCCCAGCCGUGCAUCCACCGGGGCCGGGACACCGGGGCCGCCUGGCUGGGACCGCGCGCCGCCGCCGCCGCCGGGGUCCGCUGCUGCUGCCGCUGCUCUGUGGGGUCGAGUCGCUUCAUGCAAAUGCCCGGCUCUCUGCAAACAGGCCCCCGCCUUGCAAAAGCCACUCGGCGGGCGCGCGGCCCGAGCCCCGGCGGCCGCGAGCUGGGGCUGACGGCGAGGCAAGGACCCAGCCCUCGCACCAGUUGCGCCUCGGCCUCUGCAGACGCCGGGGUGGGAUCUCGCCGCACGGCCGCGCUCGGAAUGGCACGCUCUGGUCCCCUCCCCUCUCUCCCUCCCUCCCCACCCCUUCGCCGCACGAAUUGCAGUCCCCGCCGCUGGGAGAGCUCCCCCUGCCUGUGGCUCUGCUCAGUUCCUUCCAGAAUGAACCACCCCUCCCAAGCAGGGCGCUAAGGCAAACCCGCGCCCGCGUGUGUUUCCCUGGUUCCUUGAUGCAGAGAAGCGACCCGCCAUGACACGGCCCCGGGACCACCACUGUCGCCCAGCCGCAACUUUGCAGCCUCCUUCCCCCAAAUGUAAUUUUCUCUCUCUCUCUCUUUUUUUUUCCUUAAUGCAGCAUGAUCAGUGUCCGCAGCGCGAACUGGAGACACGCAUUGUCUCGGGGCUUGCGCACGCACUGGCACACUCACAGUCGCACACACACGCGCGCGCACCCCAACUCCUUCCUUGCCCCGGCUCCUAUUACCUCAUCCUCUCCCGCAUCCUUAGCUGUCCGUCAAGGAAGCAGAAGACACGCCCCCUGCUGCUCGGGCGAGUGCCCUGGAGCUUACCCGCCCCCUGCUGGCCUAAAGUGUCGUGUGCCGGCCAGUGGCCACUCCAACCUCUGCUAAUGAGACCCAGUCCAAAGGGAUGCAGCAAUUUCGCUAAUGAUGGAUUUAUAUUACCUACGUAGAGAGCAAAUGUGGUUUUUCUGGCCAGAUUCAACGUACUAGAGUCAGGAAGACGCAUGUUAGAUUAAUUUUAUCUGCAUCGUUUCUGUAACUAAAAUUAUGAAACACUAGGAAAAACACGAGUUAGACUUAUUUUGAUCAUCAAUAGUUAAUAUGGAAAAUAACCUUAAAUAGGUAGGUUCUGACUAAAAGGGAAGACUGAAGUCAGGAUUAUGCAUUAUCCUUGUCAAAGAACACAAAUUUUGUUUUGUUGAGAUUGCAAACCACAUAAAACAACGAAUCGAGUCUUAUCAAGAUCCAAGUUAUAGGAUGCGGGAAAGUAAAAAUAGAUUAUGUGUUAGAGAAUGGGAUUGUGAAUCUUUUUGAAAUAAUCAAUUUUUUCAUAAAUAUCAUAUGACCCUUUUAUGUUUUAGAAGAGUUGCUUCCCCCUCCCUCUCCUUGCAGCUGUCAUUUCUCCCAUUGUUAGAAUUUUGCAUCCUUCUACCUUUAUCUUUCUCCCAACAGAGUUCUAAAUACAAAGCAAAAGAAAAAGUGUGAGAUCUGUUCUUCUUCAGGCCCCUAAAGGCACCAGGCUCAAGGAACCUCUGAGCUUUGUUCUUUCUGGUCUUCUUGCACAGCUUGGCCUCCAAAAUGCCUAGUCGGCCUCUCCCUUAUUUGGGGACUGUUCCUAAUCCAACCUAAACAAUACCACUCAUUAAAAUGUCGAGUUUCAGAAUUAGAAGAACAAAAAGAAAACAAGGAUACCUCGACUAAUUAUAUCAUAGGCCAUUAUUAUUACCAUUUUACAAAUGACAGGACUUAAGGAAUUUAAACUAUUUGCCCUAGAUUACAUAGCUAGUUAGAGGGGAAACCAGUAUUCAAAAUUUAGUUGGGCUGUCUCAAAAGAAAAUGCCUGUUCCAUAGCAUGUCCUAUACAACACAGAGGUGGCACAAUAACAGGCAAUGUAGAAGUGUCUCAGUGUGAAAGAAGGGAAGGGAGAAAAUGGGGGUAGAAUUUUCUGGAAAAGAAACAGAAGGCAAACUGAAGAAAAAGUAAUUUAAAAAUUUAUUGGGCUACUUUUAUUUCUAGUCAUAAAAAUGGAAAGUAUCAAAACUCAGGAAACUUUCUUAUAGUCUUGGUAAGUAUGAAUCAAAAAGUGAAGAGUAAUGAUUCAAGGGGAUAUUGGAAGUACCAGCGAAAAUAUAGCACCUGACCAGCUAAGCCAGAAAUUCCAAGGUGAAAAAAAUCUAAACUAGAUAAGCAGGCUACCAGCAAAUGUUAGAUGAGCUGUUUGAAAGGCGAAUGGAAGGCAGAAGGAAACUGACGCCUACCUGCCUAUGUCCAGCCUAGUUUUGUAUCUGGUCUUCUUGUAUCUUCCAUGUUAAACACAACAGAGUAUUACAGCAGAAUAAAAAUAUCUUAUGACAUGUGA